AGGACCCGAGGCAGGCUCUGGGCCCGCCGGGUCCGUUAAUCUCACCGCGCCGCAAGGGGCCACGUUUUACCACUUGAUUUAGCAACCCUAAGCGGUUUGGAAUCUGCUUUGCUCUCACAGGACCUCAGCCCGUCGUGAUCAGAUUCUCCCACUUUCUUUUUUCUUUCCUGGAAUGGAGUGGGCAGUCUUUUUCCAUCUCUACCGAAGUUGAUGUUCAUUUUUAAUCUUUUCGCCCCUCACGCUUUUGUAAUAAUGGUACUAAGACUGAGUGUUAUUUAGAUUUUAUUGUUGUUGUUUGUGUUUAACGCGAACUAUUUAGGCAGCCCAGGGAUAAUGCUGGCCAUAUAGAGAUGCGCCUGAUUAGGUCUCAGGAGUCAAUUCGGACUGGGCAGCUGUUGAUUUUCCAGAGCACUAGAAUGCUGCAGGGUUGGCCUUUGGCCUAAACCAUUUCUAGCUAUGGACUUGCCAGAUGAGAGCCAGUGGGACGAAACCACCUGUGGCUUGGCUGUUUGUCAGCACCCACAAUGCUGGGCAACUAUCCGCCGCAUUGAGAGGGGCCAUCCUCGAAUCCUCGGCUCAUCCUGCAAAACUCCCCUGGAUGCUGAAGAUAAACUCCCAGUGCUCACCGUGGUAGACAUCUUAGAUUCCGGCUUUGCAGCUCAUCAUUUACCAGAAUGUACCUUUACUAAGGCCCAUUCUUUAUUGUCUCAGAGUUCAAAGUUUUACUCCAAAUUUCAUGGCAGGCCUCCGAAGGGUUUACCUGACAAAAGUUUGAUCAACUGUACUAACAGACUUCCCAAAUUUCCAGUGUUGAAUUUGAAUGAGACGCAACUUCCCUGCCCUGAAGAUGUUAGAAAUAUGGUUGUAUUGUGGAUCCCAGAAGAAACAGAGAUACAUGUGAGCCAGCAUGGGAAGAAGAAAAGAAAGAACUCGGCAGUGAAAAGCAAGUCAUUUCUGGGUCUCUCUGGAAAUCAGUCCGCAGGAACACGAGUAGGAACACCAGGGAUGAUCGUGCCUCCCCCAACCCCAGUGCAAUUGUCUGAACAAUUCAGUUCAGAUUUCCUACCUCUCUGGGCUCAAUCCGAAGCGUUACCUCAGGAUCUACUGAAGGAACUUUUGCCAGGUGGAAAGCAAACCAUGCUCUGUCCAGAGAUGAAGAUAAAAUUGGCCAUGAUGAAAAAGAAUCUUCCCUUGGAAAAGAACCGACCUGACAGUGUGAUUUCUUCUAAGAUGUUUCUAUCUAUACACCGCCUCACCCUGGAAAGACCAGCACUGCGAUAUCCUGAACGUUUGAAGAAAUUACAUAACCUGAAGACAGAAGGUUACAGGAAACAGCAGCAGCGGCAGCAGCAGCAGCAGCAGCAACAGAAGAAGGUGAAAACACCUAUUAAGAAACAGGAGGCUAAAAAGAAAGCCAAGAGUGAUCCAGGGAUCCAGAGCACUUCACAUAAACAUCCAGUUACCACCGUUCAUGACCGUCUCUAUGGUUACAGAACUCUGCCAGGUCAGAACAGUGACAUGAAGCAGCAGCAGCAGAUGGAAAAAGGAACCACUUCGAAACAGGAUUCCACGGAGAGACCAAAGAUGAACUACUAUGACCAUGCGGAUUUCCACCACAGUGUAAAAAGUCCUGAAUUGUAUGAAACAGAACCCACUAACAAGGACAUUAGUGCUCCAGUGGACGCUGUGCCAGAAGCCCAGGCUGCCAGGCAAAAGAAGAUCUCCUUUAACUUUUCAGAAAUUAUGGCUAGCACAGGCUGGAACUCUGAGCUCAAACUACUUAGGAUUCUUCAGGACACUGAUGAUGAGGAUGAGGAGGACCAGUCCUCUGGGGCAGAGUGAGAAGCCUCUGGAGGAAUAGACUGAAGGCAUCCCCUGGGGCAGCCGUGUUCCAAAGCGGGAUGGCUGGUAUCCUGAGGGCAGCAACGUUUCACAUAAGGGCAAGAGGAGAGGGGCUUCUGCUCUCUGGAGCCUUUACCAGGGCCUGAGCUCUGAGCUUAGGGAUUCCAUUUUCUUUGUUCACCUCUACUUGCCUCUAAAAUAAAUGUAGGAGAAAAAUCCCCAGCCUUUUUAAAUUUAGAUUAUUUCCUUUCCAUUAGGGUCAGAAUAAUUUUGGUGAUUAAACACAACUGCUUUUCAAUCAAAA